AAAAGACCUUUGGUUUUAAGGGAAGAAAAAGUAGAGGAGAGUCCAAAUAUGUUAUUUCUAAGGAACUGAUCUUUGGUUUCAAAGGUAGGCACAUCAGCUGAGGAAUGUAAGUAAGGCAAUCCAUAUAACAUUUCAUAGGGGGAUGAACCUGUAUCUCUUCGGGGAGCUGUCCUGAUUCUGAAUAAAGCAAUAGGGAGGCAUUUGGUCCAUCGUAGAUGAGUCUCUAAAAUUUAGUUAGAUGACUUGUCUGAUUCAUUCUUUCUACUCUCCUGGAGGAGGAGGGGUGCCACCGAAUGUGGUAUUCCCAUUCUAUGUCCAGCACCUGGGCCAGUUUUAUCAUAAUGUGUGCCGUAAAGUGGGUCCCAUUAUCUGAGUCAACAUUUUCUAUUAAUCCAAACCUGGGUAUAAUAUGUUCAAUUAAGGCCGUCACUAUAUUACUGGCAGUGGCCUUUGAGAAAGGAGUGGCCUCUACCCAAUGAGUGAUGUGGUCUACUAUCACUAAUAGGUAUUUUAGCCUACUGGCAGCAUUUCAAUAUAAUCAACUUGAACACUUUGGAAUGGUCUUAGCCUAGGUGUUCUUCAUCCUAGAGGUAGUUUCUUUAGGGUCUGCUUAUUAGUUUUCUUACAGAUAAUGCAGCUGUCAGUGACCUGUCUGGCCAGGGUGUAGAUCCCAGUACAUCCAUAGACUGAGGACAGCGUCACAUAGGGCCUGAGGGCCCCAGCAUGUUCCUUGGUGUAAGUGGGACAGAACUUCUUUCAUAAGGGGUUUGGAGAGCAUCUCUCUCUGAUCUGGGAGAAUCCAUCUCCCUUCUGUAUUUUCUUUAGCCCACAUUUCGCUUAGUUUUUCCUUUUAGGCUGAAGAGAAAAUAGGAGCUAAUUUGGGGGAGAGGAGGGAGGGAGUUAGAUGAAAUAUUUGUUUCACAGCCAUUGCUGCUCUUUUGGCUACCUGAUCUGCAAGAUUAUUACCUCGACUUUCAAAUGAAAAGUCAUGCUGGUGUCCAGGGACAUGUACAAUAGCUAUUUCUCCUGGUAGCUGGAGAUUAUUUAAAACACAAGUCACUAAUGACUCAUGAGCAAGCUUUUGGCCUUGGCUGUUCAUCAGGCCUCUGUCUGCCCCAAUUUUUCCAAAUGUAUGCGCUACCCCAAAAGCAUACUUACAGCCUGUAUAAGUGUUCCUAUCUCAUUUUCUGGAUAUUUAAGGGCCUGACUGAGAGCAAAUAGUUCACAGCCUUCGGCGGAAUAGUUAUCAGGUAAUUGCCCCGAUUCAGUUUCCUCAAGAGUUUCUCCAUCCACCACAGCAUAUCCACUGUGCCUGUCUCCAUCAAACAUCCGAGAGGACCCAUCUAGGAACAAAUGUUGUCUUGUUUUAUAAGGGGUUUCAGAUAGGUCUGGUCAUACCUUGGUAUCAUAAUUAAAUCUAGAUACAAAUGUUCUGUUUGCAGCAAUGGAUUCCCUCUUAAGAAUCCGGCAGGGUCAAGUGAACUAUCAGUGGUUAUAGUUAGAUAAUCUCUUUCUAAUAGGAUAGCCUCAUACUUUAAAAUCCUAGAAUCAGUCAGCCAUCUUUCCGCUUUUUGAUUUAGGAUGACAUUGACCUUAUGGGGUGUACUUACUGUUAAGUAUCCCCCAAAGGUAAUCUUUCUGCUUUCUUCCACUAAUAUGGCAUUGGCUGCCACAGACUGGAUGCACUGGGGACAGCCACUGGCAACUGGAUCUAAGACUUUGGACAGAAAGGCAACUGGUUGCCGGUGGUCUCCAUGUUGUUGAGUGAGUACUCCAAGGGCCACUCCAUUGUCUGUGCUAACAAAAAGAUGAAAGGGUUUUUCUAAAGAAGGCAGGGCUAAAACAGGGGCAGAUAUUAAUCAUGCUUUUAAUUCAUUUAUUUGGUCUACUUCAUCAGAAGUCCUUAUAAGUGGGUCUGGCCUAUUUUUAGUUAAUUUCUCAUAAAGCAAUUUACUUCUUAAUGCAUAAGAAUCAAUCCAUAAUCUACAGUAUCCAGUCAAUCCCAGAAAUAAGUUCCUGUUUUGUUUGAGGCAGGGGCAAGGAGACAUUUCCCUCGACCUGUUCAGGUCCUAUUCUCCUUUUGGCCGUGCUAAUUAGAUGACCUAAAUGUCUAACUUCUGUUUCUACAUAUUGGAGCUCUUCUUUGGAGACCCGCAGUCCCUUAGAGUAUAAAUGAUUCAGGAAGUACACAGAGUAUUCACUUACUUUUUCUAUAUCUUCUCCAGAUAUAAGUAUGUCAUCCAUAUAUAGGAUUAAUUGUAAAUGUGGUGGAGUGUCUGUCUUUCUAAUAAUCCUAUCUAGAGCAUGAGUAAAAAUAUUCAGUGAAUCCUCAAAUCCUGGGGCAAUACUAUCCACCGGUACUGCUGCUUCUGUCCUGUAUGGGGGUCCUCCCAUUUGAAUGUGAAUAGAUCUUGGCUGUCCUCAGCCAAAGGACGUGCCCAGAAAGCAUCCUUUAAGUCUAUUACAGUAAACCAUUGAUGACUUUACAGAAUUUUACUAAGGUUAAUAUAUGGAUUUGUCAUAGUAGCGUGAGUGGUUUGAACUAUUUCAUUUAUAGCUCUGAGAUCUUGUACUAAUAGGUAGGAUCCAUCAGGCUUCCUGACAGGUAGGAUAAGGGUAUUAUACGGAGACAUGCAAGGCUCUAAAAGUCCAUCUUUAAUAAGGCCUUCAAUCACAGGUUUUAGUCCUACCCGGCCUUCCAGGGAGAUCGGGUAUUACUUUCUCCGGGCUACUCCCCCUUGGAACCUUUAAAUGUAUUUGUAUCAGGGGAAUCCGUAACUCCCUUGCUUUCCUUCUCUUGACCAUAAAUCCGGAUGAAUUUUCCUCUCAUCAACAGUAGUUAGCAGGUGGAGAGAGGGAAGGAACCCCUUUGGCCCUACUUGCAGUCCAAGACCUAACUUUAGCAUUAAGUCUCUUCCUAACAAAUUAGUGCCUGCUUCAGGAAUUAAUGGAAAUUGAAUAUUAGCUGCCUCAUUUUUGUAUCUGACUUCUAUAUCUUCUAGGAUUUUGGCCUUAAACCUCUCUUCUUUCACCCCAGAUAAUAGUAGCUCUUCUGGAGAACAGCUGAGGCCACUUGGAGAAAAGCGUAAGGAAGAACAAGUAGCUCCAGAAUCAAUGAGGAAUGUUAUUAGUUAAUGGUUUGGUCCCACCUCCAAAUUUAUCAAGGGCUCUUGAUGGGACUCAAGGUGGAAAAGAAAGAGCCCCUGACUCACGUAUUCUUCCUCUCUGAAGGUUGGCAUGAGAGGAGGAAUUUCCUCUGUGGCCUUUAGGUCAGGGCAUUCUCUCUUAAAAUGGCCUGUUUUUCCACAUUUAUAAUACCUAUCUUGUCCCCCUUCUUGUUCUAUUCUGGAGAUCCUUUGUUUUAGUUUCUCUUCAUCUGCUCUACAUCUCCACCCUUUAUGACAUAUGCUGUGGUCUUCUCAUGUUCCAUUUCAACCUCGACCCCUGCCUCUCUGUGAGAUGGCACCCCUGGACACUGGUCAAAAUCUCAUCCCAGGAAUGUUUUAAAGGAAGUUGGGCUACUCACAAGUUACUACAUAAGAAAGCAAAAGAUGAAAAGGCGAAGCGAGAAGUGUCUUCCUGGACUGUGGAAGGUGAUAUUAAUACUGACCCAUGGGCAGGUUAUCGAUAUACUGGUAAACUCAGACCACAUUAUCCACUGAUGCCAACAAGGCCAGUGCCAAGUUAUAUUCAAAGACCAGAUUAUGCUGAUCAUCCCUUAGGAAUGUCUGAAUCUGAACAGGCUCUUAAAGGUACUUCUCAGAUUAAAUUACUCUCAUCUGAAGAUAUAGAAGGGAUGCGACUUGUAUGUAGGCUUGCUAGAGAAGUUUUGGAUGUUGCUGCCGGCAUGAUUAAACCAGGUGUAACUACUGAAGAAAUAGAUCACGCUGUACACUUAGCAUGUAUUGCAAGAAAUUGCUACCCUUCUCCCCUGAAUUAUUAUAAUUUCCCAAAGUCUUGUUGUACCUCAGUGAAUGAAGUCAUUUGCCAUGGAAUACCAGACAGAAGGCCCUUACAAGAAGGUGACAUUGUUAAUGUGGAUAUCACUCUUUAUCGCAAUGGUUAUCAUGGGGACCUGAAUGAGACAUUUUUUGUUGGAGAAGUGGAUGAUGGAGCACGGAAACUUGUUCAGACCACAUAUGAGUGCCUGAUGCAAGCCAUUGAUGCAGUGAAGCCUGGUGUUCGGUACAGAGAAUUGGGAAACAUUAUCCAGAAGCAUGCCCAAGCAAAUGGGUUUUCAGUUGUUCGAAGCUAUUGUGGGCAUGGAAUCCACAAGCUUUUUCAUACAGCUCCCAAUGUACCCCACUAUGCUAAAAAUAAAGCAGUUGGAGUGAUGAAGUCGGGCCAUGUAUUUACAAUUGAGCCAAUGAUUUGUGAAGGCGGAUGGCAGGAUGAAACCUGGCCAGAUGGUUGGACUGCGGUGACAAGAGACGGAAAGCGGUCUGCUCAGUUUGAGCACACCCUCCUGGUCACAGACACUGGCUGUGAAAUCCUAACCCGGCGACUUGACAGUGCACGGCCUCACUUCAUGUCUCAAUUUUAAUUUCUCCCAAGAUGGCACAUCUCAGUACCUUCUUACUGUGCUAUGCAUUUUAUUGAGAGUACAGAAAGGAAGAGGAACCUUUUUUUAAUCACUUGUUUUGUUUUGACUAUAGAUAAGAAAGGACUACAGCAUUUGAUGUGUGUCCUCAAGAACUUGUCUUGGGUCUGAAAAAGCUGAGAAGAAUAAAGGAAACAUUGCUCAACUCUUCAGCCCCCUCCCCCUGCACACCUGUUUUCUCAUUUGCCCUUUGAGCACUUUUACUUAAACUUGCUUGUAGUUGCUUUUAUCACUGCCGCAAAACAGCCAUCAAGAGCCAUCUGCUUUCCAGGUGAACAUUGGAAAUGAGAAUCUUUGAAACUUAGCAAUAUGUGUUGCACCAGAUUUUUUAAAUUAUAUAUAUGGAAAUAUAUAUGUAUACAUUUUAAGUUCUGUAUACAUAAUUACCAAACACUAUGUGACCUGGAGUUUGUGUUGUUUCUGCUCUGACAGGUUUAUAUGUUCUUACAAAUGGAUCCAUAGUUUGCAGUGAUUUAAUUCCUGGUUGGGAUUUGGCCUCCCCUCUCCCCCAUGCUAAUUAUUUACCCUUGUAAUUGUGCAUAGGGAAGCACUCACCCAAUGAGACUUUCUCCAAUGUGGACUCUGUGUGUCAGUGAAUGAAUGUAGUAAAAUUCACUUUGGAAGGUUAUCAGGCUUUUAAAAAUCUAGUUUAUGGCAAAAAUAGCCAUUUUCCAAGUGGUGGCUGACUGUUGCAGGGAAUGAGAAUUUCAUAAUACACUGCUAUUUCAGACCUCUGUUUGGUCAGAAAUGGAAAAGAAAAAGCCCCCUUUCUUCCCUUUUCUGUUUUACUUCAAGGGCAUACCUUGGAGGUGCUCAGAGAAGCGUGAAGUUUGCACUAUGGUGGAGGAUGGGGAAAGAGUUCUAAAGUGUCUCCAGCUGUGAACCCAGGAGGUCAAGUGGGCUAUUAAAAUCUAACGUUGAGUAAAUGUGAUAGUGAUGAGAAAGGAAUUUUGUGUACUGUAACCUUGCAGUAGAGAUGCAGCUGUCCUUCGUGUGUGGAAACACACCUCUCCUUUACAUAGUUGGGAACCUCAUUAGAAAUGACCUCAGCUGCCCCAUAUCUACGUUCCUUUCAGCAGUUGUCCAAGUAGGAGUGUAUCCAGUGAAGACAUAUCAAAUCACAAAGUCAUUGUCAUUAGAGUGUACUUGAUUACUGGGCAUCCUUGUAAUAUAAUUUCAUACCACUGACACAUUAUACUUGUAAGAGAACAUCUUUCCCAGAGUGCCUCAGACCUUAUUGCUUUAAAAUAUAAUAAUGUUUUCAUUACUUUUAUUAUUUGAAUGAUUUAGUAAAGUUGACUGAAUCUGGUAUAGACUUUGGGAGUAUGUGUGUGAAGUUUUUAUCAAACUGUAAUAUUUGUGAAUGGAAUGCCUUGCAAUAUGAAUGUUAAUAUAAUGUGUAAAGGGAGAUUAAAAAGUUUGAAUGAUUAUCCUA